ACCUUUCCGCGGGCCGCGGGGAUGGCGGCGCAGGGCGUAGGGCCUGGGCCGGGGUCGGCGGCGCCCCCGGGGCUGGAGGCGGCCCGGCAGAAGCUGGCGCUGCGGCGGAAGAAGGUGCUGAGCACCGAGGAGAUGGAGCUGUACGAGCUGGCGCAGGCGGCGGGCGGCGCUAUCGACCCCGACGUGUUCAAGAUCCUGGUGGACCUGCUGAAGCUGAACGUGGCCCCCCUCGCCGUCUUCCAGAUGCUCAAGUCCAUGUGUGCCGGGCAGAGGCUAGCGAGCGAGCCCCAGGACCCUGCGGCCGUGUCUCUGCCCACGUCGAGCGUGCCCGAGACCCGAGUCACUGCUGGGCUGAGGUGGCCAAUCAUCACCCACCACGUGUUCCUGACUGCGCUCCUCCUUGGCUCAGGGCAACCCUGACUCCAUCUUUGUUGAGUCAAGUGUGACAAGCUGACAGAGUUCCAAGCAUGACACCGCUGUAACCCUCACCACCACCAGGCAAGAAUGAGCAAAGAUCUCAUUCUCUGAGGAAGAACUCCCCGGAAACUCAAAAGGAGGGCCGUCCUAUCCCUGCAGGGUAUGGGGAGAAUUUUCUGGUAUUAGCAUAGAAAGGGAGCUGGAGGUACCUCUGGAAGAGCGGGGGUCCACGGCAUCUCAGACACAGGAGUCUCUGCUUGUUCAGGGUGACAGAUGGUGAAACAGAAAUGACCUAAUGGAUCUCUAGACACCCGGUUGCAUCUUUUCUCCAGGAAUCCAGUUUCCCAUUGCAGGGUAUUUGACUACACUUGAUAAGAGGCCAGGGAAGGACCAGGAUUGAGGCUGGGUGUUCUGUUGGCUGAACCCUUGUCUGGAGUCACCCUAAAAGUGAUGGCAGGGGAGUUCCUGCAAGGGACUGCCCCAAACCUUUCCAGGAUGAGAGCCAGUUGGGAUUCCAAAGGAAGAAACACUUAAUGCCAGGGUGGUCAGUCCAAAGCAUUUGUUAGGGAGCUUACAUACAGAGGGGGCUGCAGUGUACCCUCACGAGGGACAGCCAGGAAAGAGGUUGUGCCUAGGCACACCGCACUGAGGGGGUGGGGUGUGGAGUUUCUAUGAGGGUGCAAGGAAUUUGGCUGGGGUGGGACCAGUUUCCACGUGCUUAGCAACAUGUCAGAUCUUUCAGUGUUCCAGGCAACAACCUAAACGUGUAUCAGUGUCUGGUAACAUGCAAGCCCCAGCCAGGGUUUGAGCCUGCAGGGGGAACAUGUAGCUGAUUAGGUCAGAGUAGUCAAGGCACUUCCUCAGUCAGGACAAAGGAAACACUGGGGGGAUGAAAUGGGGGACCCAACACUGAGUCAGGCAGGGGACACAUGCCCUGUUUAGAGCCCACAGGCCAGACCCUGCCAGGCCAGAGCAGGGGAGAGCCCUGGCCAAGGCACUCCACAUGGGGGUCUGUGACCCCACGGGCAAGCCUGCUACCCGGGCACGUUUGUACCUUGGAGGGUCCUCUCAGUCUUGCCGAUGCUGUCAACACCCUGAGCCCAGGGAAAUCCAUCCCAUUAAAAUAAAGGUCUGGCCCAAG